CUUUCCUACCCUCAACGCCGUUCCGGGGGGCCGGGCCUGGCAAGUCCUCUUGGAACGCCUCCCUCUUGCCUUCCCCUUUUGGGGACAGAUCCCGAAGUUCGAGCAUCCCUCGGAUAGGCCGGGUGUCAGGCCUGGUCUCUCAGGCCCGUCCAGGCCCAUCUUGACGAUUCCAAGACCACCCCCUUGAGCAAGAAUGCCAUCCCCUCUGGGUCCCCCAUGCCUGCCCGUCAUGGACCCAGAGACCACCCUUGAGGAGCCUGAGACUGCCCGCCUCCGCUUCCGAGGGUUCUGCUACCAGGAGGUGGCAGGUCCCCGAGAAGCCCUGGCCCGGCUGCGUGAGCUGUGUUGCCAGUGGCUGCAGCCUGAGGCACACUCCAAGGAGCAGAUGCUGGAGAUGCUGGUGCUGGAGCAGUUCCUGGGCACACUGCCUCCCGAGAUCCAGGCCUGGGUGCGCGGUCAGCGGCCAGGCAGUCCUGAGGAGGCCGCUGCCCUAGUCGAAGGACUGCAGCAUGACCCUGGGCAACUGUUGGGCUGGAUCACAGCCCAUGUCCUGAAGCAGGAGGUGCUCCCUGCAGCCCAGAAGACAGAGGAACCACUUGGGAGCCCCCACCCCUCAGGGACAGUGGAGUCCCCUGGGGAAGGUCCCCAGGACACCAGAAUAGAGGGGUCUGUCCAGCUCAGCUGCAGUGUGAAGGAGGAGCCCAAUGUCGAUGGACAGGAAGUGGCACCCUCCAGCCCUCCACUUGCAGCACAGUCCCCUGAGGGGAACCAUGGACACCAAGAACCAGCCUCCACAUCCUUCCACCCACCCAGGAUUCAGGAGGAGUGGGGGCUGCUGGACCGGUCACAGAAGGAACUGUACUGGGAUGCGAUGCUGGAGAAGUACGGCACAGUGGUCUCCCUGGGGUUACCGCCCCACCAGCCAGAGGCACAGGCCCAGUCAGAGCUGGGGAUGCUGCUCACGGGGACAGGCGUCUGCAGAAGCCUGCGCUCGGGAAAUGAGAGUGAGGGUCCACCUGGCUGCCCAGAGGCCCAGCCGCCCCAGGGCCCAGGGCCGGCAGCCUGGGAGGGCUUGUCUGGGGCUGCCACUCCUGCCCCCACUGUGCGCCCAGGGACACCGCCAGUGCCCACUCAGCCCACACCUGCAGAGACGAGACUGGAGCCGGCUGCCACCCCCAGGAAGCCCUACACGUGCGAGCAGUGUGGCCGCGGCUUCGACUGGAAGUCAGUGUUCGUCAUCCACCACCGGACACACACGAGUGGGCCAGGUGUGCAGUCCCCGGGGCUAGCCACCGGGGAAAGCACAGAGAAGCCACCACAAGGGGAGGUGGCCUUUCCGCACCACCCCCGACGCUCACUCACAGGCCCCCGGAGUUACCCGUGUGAGGAGUGCGGGUGCAGCUUCAGCUGGAAGUCGCAGCUGGUCAUCCACCGCAAGAGCCACACAGGCCAGCGGCGUCACUUCUGCAGUGACUGUGGCCGCGCCUUCGACUGGAAGUCGCAGCUGGUCAUCCACCGCAAGGGCCACCGGCCGGAGGUUCCAUGAGCAGCCAGACAGCACAGUCCCUCGGGGCCUCGGUGUUCUCGGGGCCUGGAUACAGCCUCUGGGGCACCAGCAGAAGACUCUGGAGGCAGCAGGGGAUGCCAGAGUGAACAAGGGGUCCCAAGCCAGUUCCCUGCCCCUGGUCUGGUCUCCCCCAAAAGACCUGGGUGCAAGGAAAAGGAGCUGCUCUCUCUCUUCUUGCCCCUGCCUCCUAGAGGGAGGUCUGGGUUCCCUUCUAUGGCUGACCAGUGCCUGUGGGGUGACUGCCAAGCACCAGGCUCCCUCCCUCCCUGUGACAUGGCCUGGGCUGACAACACUCCCUCUCCUGGGACCUCCUUGCCUCAGGUGGGUGUUCAAAAACUGUGCCUUCCCACUCGUCUGUGCAGAGGCUGGGCCUGAGGUCUCAGUGUGGAGAGCAGCAGAAGACCCAGGAAAGCACAGUUGGCUUCCGUUUCUCCUGCUCCCUGUGUGUGUUAGAAUUUUAACAUAAAUUCCACUUUCAUAAUA